UUUUUUUUUUUUUUUUUUUUUUGCUUUCCAUUUGCUUGGUAAAUCUUCCUCCAUCCCUUUAUUUUGAGUCUAUGUGUGUCUUUGCACAUGAGAUGGGUCUCCUGGAUACAGCACACUGAUGGGUCUUGACUCUAUCCAAUUUGCCAGUCUGUGUCUUUUAAUUGGGGCAUUUAGCCCAUUUACAUUUAAGGUUAAUAUUGUUAUAUGUAAAUUUGAUCCUGUCAUUAUUAUGCUAGCUGGCUAUUUUGCCCAUUAGUUGAUGCAGUUUCUUCAUAGUGUUGAUGGUCUUUACAUUUUGGUAUGUUUUUGCAGUGGCUGAUACCGGUUUUUCCUUCCCAUGUUUAGUGCUUCCCUCAGGAGCUCUUGUAAGGCAGGCCUGGUGGUGACAAAAAUCCCUCAGCAUUUGCUUGUCUGUGAAAGAUUUUAUUUCUCCUUCCCUUAUGAAGCUUAGUUUGGUUGGAUAUGAAAUUCUGGGUUGAAAAUUCUUUUCUUUAAGAAUGUUGAACAUUGGCCCCCACUCUCUUCUGGCUUGUAGAGUUUCUGCAGAGAGAUCCACUGUUAGUUUGAUGGGCUUCUUUCCAUGGGUAAACCGACCUUUCUCUCUGGUUGCCCUUAACAUUUUUUCCUUCAUUUCAACCUUGGUGAAGCUGACAUUUAUGUCUCUUGGGAUUGCCCUCCUUCAGGAGUAUCUUUGUGGUGUUCUCUGUUUAUCCCAAAUUUGAAUGUUGGCCUGUCUUGCUAGGUUGGGGAAGUUCUCCUGGAUAAUAUAUCCUGAAGGGUGUUUUCCAACUUGGUUCCAUUCUCCCCAUCACUUUCAAGUAUACCAGUAAAAUGUAGGUUUGGUCUUUUCACAUAGUCCCAUAUUUCUUGGAGGCUUUGUUCAUUCCUUUUCAUCCUUUUUUCUCUAAUCUUGUCUUCACACUUUAUUUCAUUAAGUUGAUCUUCAAUCUCUGAUAUCCUUUCUUUUGCUUGAUUGAUUUGGCUAUUGAUACUCGUGUAUGCUUCAUGAAGUUCUCAUGCUGUGUUUUUCAUCUUCAUCAAGUCAUUUAUGUUCUUCUCUCAACUGGUUAUUCUAGUUAGCAGUUCCUGUAACCUUUUAUCAAGGUUCUUAGCUUUCUUGCUUUGGGUUAGAACAUGCUCCUUUGGCUCAGAGAAGCUUGUUAUUACCCACCUUCUGAAGCCUACUUCUGUCAAUUUGUCAAACUCAUUCUCCAUCUAGUUUUGUUUCCUUGCUGCCAAGGAGUUGUGAUCCUUUGGAGGAGAAGAGGCUUUCUGAGCUUUGAAAUUUUAAGCCUUUUUGGGCUGAUUUUUCCUCAUCUUUGUGGAUUUAUCUACCUUUGGUCUUUGAUGUUGGAGACCUUCAGAUCGAGUUUUUGCGUGGUCAUCCUUUCUGUUGAUGUUGAUACUAUUGCUUUCGUUUGUUAGUUUGCCUUCUAACAGUCAGGCCCCUCUUCUGCAGGUUGGCUGGAGUUUGCUGGAGGUCCACUCCAGCCCCUGUCUGGUUAUCACCAGUAGAGGCUGCAGAACAGCAAAGAUUGCUGCCUGCUCCUUCCUCUGGAAACUUUGUCCCAGAGCGGCACCUGCCAGAUGCCAGCCAGAGCUCUCCUCUUUGAGGUGUCCGUAGACCCCUGCUGGGAGGCAUCUCCCCCUCAGGAGGCACGGGGGUCAGGGACCCACUUGAGGAGGCAGUCUAUCCCUUAGCUGAGCUCAAGCACUGUGCUGGAAGAUCCACUGCUCUUUUUAGAGCCAGCAGGCAGGAACGUUUAAGUCUGCUGAAGACGCACCCACAGCUGCCCCUUCCCCCAGGUGCUCUGUCCUAGGGAGAUGGAAGUUUUAUCUAUAAGCCCCUGACUGGGGCUGCUGCCUUUUUGUCAGUGAUGCCCUGCCCAGAGAGGAGAAAUCUAGAGAGGCAGUCUGGCUACAGCAGCUUUGCUGAGCUGCAGUGGGCUCCACCCAGUCGGAACUUCCCAGUGGCUUUGUUUACACUGUGAGGGGAAAACCACCUACUCAAGCCUCAGUAAUGGCGGACGCCCCUCCCCCCACCAAGCUUGAGUGUCCCAGGUCGACCUCCGACUGCUGUGCUGGCAGCAAGAAUUUCAAGCCAGUGGAUCUUAGCUUGCUGGGCUCUGUGGGGAUGGGACCUGCUGAGCAAGACCACUUGGCUCCCUGGCUUCAGCCCCCUUUCCAGCCCCGAUGUAAAAUGUAUAUCCCACUGGACCCUGAUUACAAUGCAGACUGCCCCAAUGUGACAGCACCUGUUUGUGCCUCAAAUGGCCACACUUUCCAGAAUGAGUGUUUCUUUUGUGUUGAACAGAGGGAAUUUCAUUAUCGUAUAAAAUUUGAAAAAUAUGGAAAAUGUGAUUAAUGGGUACCAGAGUAACUACACUUGCUUAUUCUUUUUCUACUUAAUUCAGAAUAGUAUUUCUUUUAGAGUGUGAGAAUGUAAAUUAAAUAACAUCCCUAUGCUGUACUUAAAUGUCGAACAAAAUGAGAGACAAAAAUGAAGGAAUCAAACUGACAAGAACCAAAUAUCACAUUUGUUACAAAUAAACAACAAAAGAGCUGAUAUUCA